ACUUUCAGUAAGUUGUGACCAGUAUGUCUGGACGUGGCAAGCAAGGCGGUAAAGCUCGCGCCAAGGCCAAGACCCGCUCUUCUCGGGCUGGGCUUCAGUUCCCCGUGGGCCGAGUGCACCGCCUGCUCCGCAAGGGUAAUUAUGCCGAGCGGGUUGGAGCCGGCGCGCCAGUGUACCUGGCUGCGGUGCUGGAGUACCUGACCGCUGAGAUCCUGGAGCUGGCUGGCAAUGCGGCCCGCGACAACAAGAAGACCCGUAUCAUCCCGCGUCACCUCCAACUGGCCAUCCGCAACGACGAGGAGCUCAACAAGCUGCUGGGCAAAGUCACCAUCGCGCAGGGUGGUGUCUUGCCCAAUAUCCAGGCCGUGCUGCUGCCUAAGAAGACUGAGAGCCACCAUAAGGCCAAAUAAGGAGCGAGGUUGUGAAAACUGGAAAACAAAGGCUCUUUUCAGAGCCA